GCAGUUCCCAACACUUCUCGUCAUCCUCUCUUUGGUCUCUUUAUUCUGCUGAGCGGUGCUGUUAGGAUUUCUUUUUUUUUUUUUUCCCCUGACCACGUUCGCGAUGGUGGGUAGCAGCAAGGUGGCCCUGGUAGGGGAGGGGUUGGUAUCGAGAUUGGGCACCGGAGGAGAACGCCUUCUUUCAACUUUGUCUGUGGCUUGCACCCCCGGAGAAGGCCACAGGCCGGUUGUCGGGUGCAGAUGUGCCGAGAGUGAUUUCUAAGUAGUUGAGUUGUUGUGAUGAGGGUACGACUGCUAAUGGUCGGCAGGUUUUGUUUUCAUUGGUGAAUCUGGUGUCAUCAUAUUCCGGUCAUAUGUUGAAAUAUUCUUUGUUUAGGUCUGGAAGUAGAGGAUCUCACUCUGCACGUCCACAUUGUGUUGUUUUUAAAAUGAUGUCUCUGGGAGUCUGGAUUUCUAGAAUUUCAAAUCUGAGUGAAGGUCCGGGCAUGUGUGGGCCUCAUCACCUGGCCUUGACAGUGAACUUUGUGGCUGUGUUUCAGAUUUCAAAGAUUUGCCCCAUAGCUGGGGAAGGAGUUGUGCAUUUUUGCUAAUAGUCGGUGUCAGGAAUGUAGAUGCUCGAGCUGGGAAAGUUAGAGAGGGAAGAACAUUUAUAUAUAAAUAAUGGAUAGUUGAAUAUUAGAAUCAGAUUAAUUUGGGCUGAUGAAAGUUUUUUUUUUUUAAAGCAGUUGUGCACUCUGGGAAGGAAGUCUUUUCACAGGUUCACUUGAUAGGGAUUCUUUAAGGCGAGGGGCUGGAAUUAUCUCCUUUUUGAGCGAGUUCUCACCAACAUCUGUAGCUUUAUUGAGGGCCUGGUAAGGGUACUGAAAUUGAGGCUAAACCAUGUAAGCGUACUUUUCAGUGUUUAUGAUAUUUGUUUACAUCUGGUGUUCACUCUAAGCAAUAGAAAUAAAUAGGUCAGCUUUGCUUUUGGUCUUUGAAGACUGGCCCCCUCCUUCCUUUUUUAAGUUUCACAAUUUAUUUGGUUUACAGCAUUGUUGGAAACUGUUACUACAUUUUUACUGGAAAUACUAUUAUUCAUUUUAAUUUUGGGGGCUAGAGAGCUGAAGGAGAGCCAGUUUCCCCAAAAUUGGACUUCUCAGAACCUUUAAUAUGCUAAUGUGCAUUGUGAAUCUCCAAGAGGGGGAUAUGAUAUGCAGCAUUCUUGAAUACUUCUAAUGACAGGGAGCCCACUACCUCAUAAGCUGCAGUGAGAAGAGGAGUUUGUUACUUUAAACAGAGGCUGAAGAAACUAUAGAAUUAGCAGAGAAAGUGGAGAAGGUAGAGGAUGGAGUUGCAGACUCUACAGGAGGCUCUUAAAGUGGAAAUUCAGGUUCACCAGAAACUGGUUGCUCAAAUGAAGCAGGAUCCACAGAUAUUUUUUCUUUCCAAUCAGAAUGCUGACUUAAAGAAACAGCUUCAUGAACUCCAAGCCAAAAUCACAGCUUUGAGUGAGAAACAGAAAAGAGUAGUUGAACAGCUACGGAAGAACCUGAUAGUAAAGCAAGAACAACCGGACAAGUUCCAAAUACAGCCAUUGCCACAAUCUGAAAACAAACUACAAACAGCACAGCAGCAACCACUACAGCAACUACAACAACAGCAGCAGUACCACCACCACCACGCCCAGCAGUCAGCUGCAGCCUCUCCCAACCUGACUGCUUCACAGAAGACUGUAACUACAGCUUCUAUGAUUACCACAAAGACACUACCUCUCGUCUUGAAAGCAGCAACUGCGACCAUGCCUGCCUCUGUGGUGGGCCAGAGACCUACCAUUGCUAUGGUGACCGCCAUCAACAGUCAGAAGGCUGUGCUCAGCACUGAUGUGCAGAACACACCAGUCAACCUCCAGACGUCUAGUAAGGUCACUGGGCCUGGGGCAGAGGCUGUCCAAAUUGUGGCAAAAAACACAGUCACUCUGCAGGUUCAGGCAACACCUCCUCAGCCCAUCAAAGUACCACAGUUUAUCCCCCCUCCUAGACUCACUCCACGUCCAAACUUUCUUCCACAGGUUCGACCCAAGCCUGUGGCCCAGAAUAACAUUCCUAUUGCCCCAGCACCACCUCCCAUGCUCGCAGCUCCUCAGCUUAUCCAGAGGCCCGUCAUGCUGACCAAGUUCACCCCCACAACCCUUCCCACAUCCCAGAAUUCCAUCCACCCCGUCCGUGUCGUCAAUGGGCAGACUGCAACCAUAGCCAAAACGUUCCCCAUGGCCCAGCUCACCAGCAUUGUGAUAGCUACUCCAGGGACCAGACUCGCUGGACCUCAAACUGUACAGCUUAGCAAGCCAAGUCUUGAAAAACAGACAGUUAAAUCUCACACAGAAACAGAUGAGAAACAAACAGAGAGCCGCACCAUCACCCCACCUGCUGCACCCAAACCAAAACGGGAGGAGAACCCUCAGAAACUUGCCUUCAUGGUGUCUCUAGGGUUGGUAACACAUGACCAUCUAGAAGAAAUCCAAAGCAAGAGGCAAGAGCGAAAAAGAAGAACAACAGCAAAUCCGGUCUACAGUGGAGCAGUCUUUGAGCCAGAGCGUAAGAAGAGUGCAGUGACAUACCUAAACAGCACAAUGCACCCUGGGACCCGGAAGAGAGGUCGUCCUCCAAAAUACAAUGCAGUGCUGGGGUUUGGAGCCCUUACCCCAACAUCCCCCCAAUCCAGUCAUCCUGACUCCCCUGAAAAUGAAAAGACAGAGACCACAUUCACUUUCCCUGCACCUGUUCAGCCUGUGUCCCUGCCCAGCCCCACCUCCACAGACGGUGAUAUUCAUGAGGAUUUUUGCAGCGUUUGCAGAAAAAGUGGCCAGUUACUGAUGUGCGACACAUGUUCCCGUGUAUAUCAUUUGGACUGCUUAGACCCCCCUCUGAAAACAAUUCCCAAGGGCAUGUGGAUCUGUCCCAGAUGUCAGGACCAGAUGCUGAAGAAGGAAGAAGCAAUUCCAUGGCCUGGAACUUUAGCAAUUGUUCAUUCCUAUAUUGCCUACAAAGCAGCAAAAGAAGAAGAGAAACAGAAGUUACUUAAAUGGAGUUCAGAUUUAAAACAAGAACGAGAACAACUAGAGCAAAAGGUGAAACAGCUCAGCAAUUCCAUAAGUAAAUGCAUGGAAAUGAAGAACACCAUCCUGGCCCGGCAGAAGGAGAUGCACAGCUCCCUGGAGAAGGUAAAACAGCUGAUUCGCCUCAUCCACGGCAUCGACCUCUCCAAACCUGUAGACUCUGAGGCCACUGUGGGGGCCAUCUCCAAUGGCCCGGACUGCACCCCCCCUGCCAAUGCCGCCACCUCCACGCCGGCCCCUUCCCCCUCCUCCCAGAGCUGCACAGCGAACUGUAACCAGGGGGAAGAGACUAAAUAACAGAGCCCCUCUAGGAGAAGCCACGGGAUCCCGGCGGCAAGGAGAACAGAACACUGAAGACUCUAGAAAAGCAAAGCCGGAUUUCUGGAAAGUGCAGAAUUCUUUUGGUUCUUUGGUUCCAGAGAGAGAGAAGAUGCUUGUGCCAGGUGGCACCAGAGUUUGCCAAUUGAUCCUUCUUAUUCUGUGUGUACAUGCAAAGAUUGGACCAUGUUACAUGAAAUAGUGCCAGCUGGAGGUUCUUUGCCAGCACCAUGCCAAGUGAAAUAAUAUAUUUACUCUCUCUAUUAUACACCAGUGUGUGCCUGCAGCAGCCUCCACAGCCACGAUGGGUUUGUUUCUGUUUUCUUGGGUGGGGAGCAGGGACGGGCGGAGGGAGGAGAGCAGGUUUCAGAUCCUUACUUGCCGAGCCGUUUGUUUAGGUAGAGAAGACAAGUCCAAAGAGUGUGUGGGCUUUCCUGUUUCUAAACUUUCGCUACUAUAAAACCAAAAAAAGGAAUUGAGAUUUCACCAACCCCAGUGCCCAGAAGAGGGAAGGGGAGUGGCUGGAGGGAGCAGGGGGUGGGACAGUGUAUCAAAUAAGCAGUAUUUAAUCACCUCUGGCGGGGGCCUCGUGCAAGGGGAGACUGACACCAAGAACAGCCAGUAGGUUCUUCUCCCCUGCACUCUGCUCCCUGCGCGGUAACCCCACCACUCCUGAAGCCUGCCCAGUCUCCUUCCUUCCCUGCUUGGUGAGUCGCGCAUCUCCGUGGUUAUCCCGCUGUCUCCUCUCCAAGAACAAGCAGAGCCCGGGCCACUGGCCCUUGCCCAAGGCAGGGAAGAAGGAUGUGUGUGUCCAGGAAGGAAAAAAAGGUGGAUCAGUGAUUUUACUUGAAAACAAGCUCCAUCCCUUUUCUAUAUUUAUAAGAAGAGAAGAUCUUGAGUGAAGCAGCACGCGACCCAGGUGUGUGUGAAUUGAAUGGAGACGUUUCUUUUCUCUUUCUUUAAUUUUUGUUUUUGUUCUUUUUUUCUUUAAGGAAAGUUUUAUUUUACUGUUCAUUUUACUUUCUUGGUAACAAAAACUAAAAUAAGGAAUAGAAAAGCUGUUUUUCAGGCUGACAGUCCAAUUAAGGGUAGCCAAGACCUUGCAUGGUAGAGUAGGAAUCAUAGUGUCAGUGAGGUCCCGUGAGUCUUUGUGAGUCCUUGUGUCAUCGUUCGGGCACUGUUUUUUUAUGCAAGGGCAAAAAUCUUUGUAUCUGGGGAAAAAAAACUUUUUUUUAAAUUAAAAAGGAAAAUAAAAGAUAUUGAGGUCUUCCUAGUGUUACUUAAAUUAAGAUCAAGGUAAGAAACAUUGUAAAAAAAAAUUACAAAAGUGCUAUUUGUUUCCUAAAAACAGUGAUUUCUAUUAAAAAGGUGUCAGAACUGGAGAAAAUGCCGUGUAGUUAUAAUUUUUUAGCACAGACCCUGCUGAUCACGAUGACAUUUUGCCGUGUGUGUGUCUCUAGACUGGUGGGCCAGUCUCCUUGAAGGACAGAGGCGGAGCUCCCCACCCUUCUCUCUCCUCAGAAAAGACCGUGCUCUCUUCUUGGUGCAGGGAUCUUGUCUCCUGUUGUGAAGCCCAAAUGGAAGCGUGGAUGGUAUCAGGGCCCUACCCGUGGUCUUCUCAGAUUCUGCUAGAGCAAAAGGCUGGUGCCUAAAUAAGAUCCCUUCCUUUGGUGCUGCUUUUGGUCUUUCAGCCACCAGCAUUAUGAGUGCCUGGGGGACACCUCCGAGGGAACUGGCCAGCGGAGCUCUGUGGUGCGCACGCACCCUGGCCGUGACAGGAGGGUGCGGGAGUACAGGCUGGCUGCAUCAGCCCUUGGUGCUUAGAACAGAGGAGGAGUGACAUGUUUUGAGGGUACGUCUCUGAGACAGAGCCCCAGCGUGGCCUUCGCUCUGUCUUGCCUUUGGGGAGAGGUCUGAAGCUCCCACUCCUUUCUCUGCCUGUUGGCUCCAGGCACCAGAAAUUUACUCCACUCCACCCACCCACAAGCCUCCUGGGUGACCCUGGGCUAGAAUUGCUGCGCUUGCCUCGGCUUGGCCGGUUGUGGCCUCUCCUUGAGAAAACCAGGGUUGUGAAAGACUCAGACCAUUCUCUCAUCUUGCCUUGUCAGAAGUAAAUUGUGUCAGAUUUGUGCUCUCGCUGGAGACCUUUGCCCCUUGCGUGCCCCUGGCCGAUGGGAGGGCGGUGGAGGCUCUGUACCCUGGCCCUGCUGGAGCAUCUCCCCCAAGCCCACUCCAGGCCCUGGGAAUGGCCAGAGUCUAGGAGAGGUAGAAACGAUCCUAUCAGCUUCUCUCCCACCCAAUUAGGCCCAGAGAGACAAAGACAGAUCUGAAAGCAAAUGCAACAGAGAAGAGACACUUCUUAGAGUAAAAUGUGUCUCAUCUCUAUCAGCCAUCGCCUUUCAUCUUCCCAGGGGCCUCAGAAGAAGGAAUUAAGUUAGGCUGAACAGGCCUCAGAGUUAGGCCCUGGCUGCUUGAUUGGCUGAGGGGGAAAGAGUUCCCUUUUCUCAUUCAGAAACCAAGGUGCUGUGUCUAGUCAGGGAGCCUUGGAGAUGCCUGGACUAGUUGGAGGAAUCGUUGGCAGAGGAUCAGAGACCAGCAGCAGGCUGUCUGCCCUGUCUAGAGCUCUUCCCCUCAACUUGUCUGGGCCCAUCUGGGGGUUGCCACACAACACCUAACUUACCUUUUCCUGAAAGAAGUUGGGAAACCAUCAUCACUAGAGGCCUUUGCUCAGAGAGGAGCUGCCUUAGGAGUCUUGGGUCGGAGGACGGGGCUAGGAAUUGACCAGGGCUUUGCCUGCCGCCCUCAGCAGUGUCGGGUACAUUCUGACCUCGCCUGCAGCUGGGCUGUGGAUUCUUCCUGACAUUCAGAUGUGAGCUGUUUUGGGAGUCAGCUAGUAUGGAGUACGAGAUGCAACCCAGCCCCCAAACCUACAUUCUGCACUCAAAUUCCAAAACACUGCUUUACUGUAAAGAAGAGGCCCCUGGCACCCAAUCUCCCUGUCCUUCACUGUCCCCUCAGACCUGGGCGGGGAGGGGGGGGGGCCUGUGACCACCUGAGACAUACGCUCGUGACACUGCCCCACCCCAGCCACCUCCACUUGCUUCCUCCUCCUUCCCUCCGCUGCUCUUUCCCCACGGCCCAGAAUUUAGCUGCUCUGACAGCCACUUUUGAGACCAGCUGGCUUUGUAGUCACUUCAGAGAGCUGGAGCGGCUGCCCACUGGGCCCUGACUGGGAGUCCCCUGCCAGCUCCUGAUCAGGCGCUGCGCCCUGGUGGCAGUGAUGACUGGGAGUCCCCUGCCAGCUCCUGUCCAGGCGCUGCAUCCUGGUAACAGUGAGGCCAUGUUGCUGUCAUCUCCACCUCUGCAUUCUUGCUGCCUGUGGGUCCUUUUUCUUUCAUGGAGCCUGCUGGGUCUUGUCUCACCUGUGCUGAGCUCCUCUGGGGUUUUGAUUUCUUCCUUCCUUAUCAGGCCCUUUGGGGUAAGCCUGCUGGUUGUACCUGACAUAGGGAGGCAGUUAGGGGCAGUCCCUGGUGGGGCCGCCCUGGCAGCCUCCAGCUGGCACCAUCGUGUGCCUGGUUUCCCUGCAACACCUGCCUCUCUGUCCCUGCUGCUGCUUGGCUCAGGCCCAACAGGCAGCGUGCAUGGAGGUGGUUACACACAGCUGUUUCCGUGAGGGUGACCGUGUCUGCAGCACGCUUCCGUCUCCGCAUGCACGGCUGCCUCUCCAGCCACCUCUGAUACUUCUCUCUUGGGGCCAUCAGAGCCUCCCUUGGGCUGUCACCUCCCAGCUCACACACACUCUUCAGUGGUUUCCUCUCUUCAUUCUCUUAUAGGGCGUGGUCCUUCUUAUUUAUCUAAAGGGCUGAAUUUAGGAGACUUUUUACCCAGGGGCAAAAGGCUCUUAGGGUAAUGAGAUGGAUGGUGGCCCAGGUGCAUUUUCCAGGGCCUGGGUUCUCCAGAUCCCGUGGCUUCUGUUGAGUGGAGGCAACUUUGCUCUGUGUGAACCUCGCCCCUGUCCCUCUGCCGGGCACCCCUGGCAGGAAGCAGGACUCCCAUCCUCACCCUGACUUAGACUGUCCUCUGAGUCAGCUCCUCUCCAAGACAGGAGUGGGCAGCCCUGGGCAGUCUUCUGGCCCCUUGCUAAAGUGAGGGGCAGGAAGCUGGGGCUGCCCUCCAGAAAGCCGGGGUAGGAACUCUGAAAAAUACCUCCUCUAAACGGAAGCAGGGCUCUCCAGUUCCACUUGGCGCCCCCUCCCACAAGGCCCUUCCUCCCUGAGGACCCCACCCCCCUACCCCUUCCCCAGCAGCCUUUGGACCCUCACCUCUCUCCGGUGUCCGUGGGUCCUCAGCCCAGGGUGAGCUGCAGUCAGGCGGGAUGGGACGGGCAGGCCAGAGGUCAGCCAGCUCCUAGCAGAGAAGAGCCAGCCAGACCCCAACCCUGUCUCUUGUCCAUGCCCUUUGUGAUUUCAGUCUUGGUAGACUUGUAUUUGGAGUUUUGUGCUUCAAAGUUUUUGUUUUUGUUUGUUUGGUUUUUGUUUUGAGGGGGUGGGGGGGGAUACAGAGCAGCUGAUCAAUUUGUAUUUAUUUAUUUUAACAUUUUACUAAAUAAAGCCAAAUAAAGCCUCUCA